GCUCCGGCGGCUCCUGUCAGCGGCGGGUGCGGCGGAUCCCAGGGCAGCCUUCGGGCGGCGGCGCUGCCUGGUGCGUCGCGGCGUGGUCCUCCGGCGGCUGUCCGGGGCGGUAGGAGUUGGCUGCGGGAUGUGCUCAGCCGGGGAGCUGCUGCGGGGCGGCGACGGCGGGGAACGCGACGAGGACGGGGACGCGCUGGCGGAGCGGGAGGCGGCAGGGACCGGGUGGGAUCCCGGGGCGAGCCCGCGGCGGCGCGGACAGCGGCCGAAGGAGAGCGAGCAGGAUGUUGAAGACUCACAGAACCACACUGGUGAGCCGGUUGGAGAUGACUACAAGAAAAUGGGAACACUUUUUGGUGAACUGAACAAAAACCUUAUCAACAUGGGCUUCACAAGGAUGUAUUUUGGAGAACGAAUAGUGGAACCAGUAAUAGUCAUUUUCUUUUGGGUUAUGCUGUGGUUCCUUGGCCUGCAAGCCCUUGGACUAGUUGCUGUUCUUUGCCUUGUUAUUAUUUAUGUGCAACAGUAAAACAUGGCCGAAUUGAAUUGUUUGACAUUUGGUAGCCAUAUAUGUAAUUGAAGAAGUUAUAUAUUUCACUUUUUGACAACCGAAAAAGUUUGCCUUGUUUCAAAUCAUGUGCUGGCUGUUUUGUAAGUAAAUUUAUACAUGGAUGUCACUUAAAACUAAACUCUUGAUCAUAACAGGGUUGAAUAUAUAUUUUGAAUAUACAUUAGCUUAUUCAAAACUCUUGUUUCACUACUGUGAUCUCUGUCUCCUUUAUACACCUCUAUCCCCAUGCCAAAUCUUAAGUAACACCACCAGAAAGUGAACAGGGAAAAUAACAGGACAUGGAAUUCAAAUCAAGCAAUAUAGUUCUUAUAAAGAGUUCCAAUAAAACAUUUCAGAAGAAAAAGUAUGAAACAAGCUAAAAGUAAGUUUCACUUAGAAAACUUCUCCCCACUCACACUCCCCACCAAAUAAUCUCAUAUUAUUUGGGAAAUAUUUGGAUUUCAAUUGUCCCUACCCAGCCUAAACUAAGGUAAAUGAUAAUUAGCAUACACUACCUUAAUAUUGUGAUGAAAAUCAGUAAAGAUAGAACGUUUUCUAAAGGUCAAAAAUAAUAUAUUUAUUAUUACUGGGGAAAGCUCCCAGGUUAAAUAUAACUUUUUUAAAAUGUAACAUUUGGACCUAGACCUACUUUAAUAUAUCAUUUGAAGUUUCAGACAAUUUUGGUGCUAAUUACUUUUUGUGAGUUUUUAAAGUCUCAUAGCCUAGUUGACUGCACCCUAUGGUAAUGCCAUAUUUUCUUGUAUCUAACAAGUUGCAUAUUUUUUCCUAGAGAGACAUUUUCAGUGUAUUUUUUUUUAGAAAUUUAUAAUUUUAUAGUUCUUUCAUAACACUUAUUCUGAGUUUUGAAACAAUGUAUUUCCUAUCUUGACAUGGAUUUUUUCACAAAAAAUUUGUAUUUUACUGUUGUUUUCAGGAAAAAAAUCAGAUCAUUUUUCUUUGAUAUCUAUAUCAGAAAGGUACAAUAUUAACAGUAUAAAACCAAAUGCUUAAAUUUGGAACUUAGCCAAUUUUGAUAAUCUUUUUCUAAGGCUAAAGUCACAUCAGUAAUUGGCUAGCCAUGUUAUUAAGGUGUCUUAAUUCAGCAUUUUCAGGUUUUAUAUUGAAAUACGCAUUUCUUUAAAUAUUCUUUGAAAAUGGAGAAUGGCUUUAGUGAUAUUUUGGGUUUUGUUAGAGAACCUAAAAUCUUUACACUUUCAUCUCAAAGAUUAUAAAGGAAAGGGGGGUAGUUAAGAUUUAGAAUUCAAGUUAAAUUUCAGAAAUUGGGGCAGUCAGGCAUUUGUAUCUUUGGUAGGGCAACAAGUAAAACAUGUAGAGUGCUUGCUAUCCCACUUCAUAAAGCUUUUACCCAAUCUUAUUUCUAAACCUCUGUGCAUUCUUAGUGUCUUCUCAUUCUGAAACAGAAAAUAAGGAAAAACAUUUAACUUAGUUUUCUAAAAUCAGAUAAUCCUAAACAAAAAUGUUAGUCAGGGUCACUAAAAAGUAUUGCACAUUUAUAUAAAUACAGUCCUUUUAAAAUUUGACUUUUAAAAAACAAAAGACUUUGUACGAUAUUGUGUUUUUAUUGCUUUUGCAAUAUUUUUAUAGUAGCCUUUAUGAACUCAGUAUAAGUGCAAGUUGUUUGAAAAGGUGUUUUUAUUAGUGCACAAUAGAAUUGUGAGGUUUUCAAUAGAUGUCAUGAGAUUUUGUAUAUCUACAUAAAAUAUCAGUACAUUUUUUUCUAAUGCUACUGGAAAUUUUACUUUUCCUUUGCAACACAUAAAUGAUAUGAUGUACAAAAUAACAGCUCUGGUUCCACCAGUACCUAAUGUUGAAAACAUUUUUAAAGUAAUUUUUAAUACUAACUAUUUAGUAUACUGUCAGUACUGUACAUCUGCACACUGGUGUUAAUAGGGUAUAUAUUAAAUUAUAUAAAGAAAUAAGAUAUUUUGCUGUUAUUCUUUCUACAUAUAUUAUUGGUCAGUACAUCAAAUAAUAUUUGGCUUUGAUAUGGGAAAAAACAAACUUUGCCUAUGUAAUGGAAAUAAAAUAUUUUCUUUUAUGAAAUAUAUUAGAAUGCAGAUUAUACUAAUAUCCUGAAAUAAAACUGGUAAUUUAUUUGGUUCAUGGUAUAAAGAAUUAGAUUGGGCCGGGCGCGGUGGCUCACGCCUGUAAUCCUAGCACUUUGGGAGGCUGAGGCGGGUGGAUCACAAGGUCAGGAGAUCGAGACCUUCCUGGCUAACAUGGUGAAACCCCAUCCCUACUAAAGGUACAAAAAAUUAGCCGGGCCUGGUGGCAGGUGCCUGUCGUCCCAGCUACUCAGGAGGCUGAGGCAGGAGAAUGGCGUGAACCCGGGAGGCAGAGCUUGCAGUGAGCACUCCAGCACUCUGGGUAACAGAGUGAGACCCCAUCUCAAAAAAAAAAAAAAAAAAAAAAAAAUUGGAUUGAAAAUGAUUCUCAUCAUUUCAAUCUCAAAUACAAGCCAGUUUUAGAAACUGUUAUUGCUUAUGAAUAAAGAAAUAGAAGUUACAAUGCUAAGGUUAUUACAUAAUGCAUACUCAUAUGGCCAGUAAUUCAAAAGAAAAAGGUCGAAGUCUACAAAUAAACAGACUGUAGAUGAGUAAAUCCAUUUUUCUUAAAGUAAAAACUCUGUAUUUUGUAGAAUUCUGUCCUCUCAUACCUUAAGCUGUCAUGGGCAAGGUAUUUUCCCAUUCCUGGCUACAGGCAGAUCAUUCCUAGUCCAGUAGUGUGCUGGAGCAAGCUUGCACUGGCUUACAAGAGCCAACUGUGAACAUUUUUUCUGCCUUCAGUGCUGUCAAGUUGGUAGUUUGAAAUUGGCCAUGGUGAGAGUAUUUACACCAAAAAAAUUAGUAAACACUGCAAAUCAGAUCUUUUUUUUUUUUUUUUCCUUGAAAGCCAGCUGUUAAACAUACAUCAGCACACCCUAGAGGCCACAUUCCCAUUUCUAUUCCUACAGAUACGAAAGUAAAGAACAGAACACAUUUUGUGAAAUAAAAGAAAGCAUAUGAGGUAAAUCCCCAUCGACCCACCCAAAACUGAAUCUGGCUCUUUCCCUUGUGGGUAUUAUGGUUCAUGGUUAUCUUCUGACCAACAAAUCUCUAUUUAAUCAUGUUUUGACCACAGAAAAUCUCUCUAGGCUGUCACCAAGCUGUAAAUCCACUAAAGACUAUCCAGGCAAUCAGGAAAGGCAAAACUUACAGAAUGAUAGAGGAAAAAUUACAGUAUAAGUAAAGGUCUGUUGUAAUAUAGAAAGCUCAAAAUAGUCAAAGCCAGGUUUGGAGCAAUCAAAGGCUAUUCGUGUGGUUCAUAGAUUGUUUUAAUAGUUAUUUUACAAAUGUUUAUUAAUUUCAGGUGUUUAAAAUGCUUUCAUUACCAAUUUAUGGCUUUACAAUUGAAGGGAGAAAAAAAAAUGUAAGACGGCCAGGCGCGGUGGCUCAUCCCUAUAAAAGUGCUGGGACAGCACUUUGGGAGGCCGAAGCGGGCGGAUCACCUGAGGUCGGGAGUUCGAGACUAGCCUGACCAACAUGGAGAAACCCCGUCUCUACUAAAAAAAAAAAAAAAAAAAUACAAAAUUAGCUAGGCGUGGUGGUGCAUGCCUGUAAUCUCAGCUACUCAGGAGGCUGAGGCAGGAGAGUCGCUUGAACCCGGAAGCCAAAGUUUGCAGUGAGCCAAGAUUAUGCCCUUGCACUCAAUCUGGGCAACAAGAGCGAAACUCCAUCUCAAAAAAAAAAAAAAAAGACUUUCAUGCCUGGUAAUAGAGUUGGCCGAGAAGAAUAUAAACUUAUUUACAAACUAUGACUUCAGGAGUAUUGGUGGAUUAGAGGUCAUUUGCAACUCUUGUCUCUCUGCCCAACAUUUAAUUUUUGGUAUGCGUUGGAGUUCAGUCCAACAGCCUGCUCUCACAUCACUCCACACAGCAGCUCGGCAAUGUCACCACUCCCGUGGCUGCAGAGUUACCAUUUGCAUCCUAACAGCUCCCCAAUUUGCAUCUCUAGAUCAGAGCACUGUACAGAAUUUAAGACUCCUACAUUCAAUUGCUUGCCCAAUAUUUAUUUGCAUUUGGUUAUCCCAUAGUACCCAAGACUCAGCGUGUCCAAACGAGCGCAGCAUCCUUCUCCCAAAUCUUUAAUUCCUGUUUCCCAUCUCAGCAAAUGACACAAUCCUUUCCCUAACUGCUCAAGCAGGAGUUGUAGAUGACAUCCUUGACUCUGUGUUUCCUACACUACCUACAUGUAACCAAGUACCAAAUCUAUUUUACUUCUAAAAAUAUAAUCUUUCUACUUCUAUUCAUUCCUAGCAUCACUGAGUCCAUUCUGCCAUCAUCUCACCUGGCAUGCUGAGAAUCCUGAUUAGCCUCCCUACCUUCAUUUUCCACUUUGUAGUUACAGAUCUUUCUAAAGAAUUAUUCUAACAUGAUUCUGAUAUCCUUGACCUAAAUCUUUUCAAUGGCUUUCUGUUUUCGUUAUGAUAAAGUCCUUAUGCCUUAAUAUGUUUUACAAGGCUCUUCAUGUACUGGUUCUUGCGUACCUCAUCUCUCUAUACUGCCACUCUCCAUUUCCAGGAUUCAACUAUACUGAACUUUUCCCCAGUUCCUUUAAAGAGACAUGCUUUCUUACUUCCAGAACUUUGUACAUGCUUUACUUCUUUAACUGCUCCCUACCAGACUGACCAAUAUCUACACAGCCUUAAGACCUCAAGUGAGACAUCAUGUCCUCCAGGGAAACUUCUCUGACUCCUUUAAAUCCAGUUUUGGUUCUUCAUUAUGGCUUGGUUUCUCAAGUGCAACCCUGUGCUUUCCAGGUCAGCACUUCUCAUGCUAUAUUGCAAUAGCUUAUUUGUCAGCUGCUGCUUUAAUAAUUGAUUAAUUAUUAAAUUAAUCAAUAGGCUUCACAAGGGAAGAGAACAUGUCUGUCAUUCUAUAAUUGCAUUGCUAGUGCCUAACACAAUGCCUGGGACAUAAUAGGCCAUCAAAAUAUUUAUCAAGUAAACCCACUUCAUCUACUCAUGGUCUUCAUAUAGACCACUAACAAAAAAGAUCUAGAGCUGGUUGUACUUUGAAGUUCUUUGACUCCAAAAGUAUACUUACUGUGCACAAAGAGCAUGGGUUGAUGUAUACAUUAUAAUUUAUAAAGCUAUUCACUUCUGAUAAAAGAAUACUGCUGUUAUUUGGAUACAUACACAGUAUUUCCACUAUACACUUGUGUAUUUUAGGAGAAAAUGUAUUUUCAAUGUUUGGUUGAUUCACUAUUUUUCCAAAAAGGAUAUUUUACAAUACCUACGGUCACUGAUACUACCAGAACUUCACUUUUGUUCAGUAUUUUUUAAUAGACCUUUAUUUACUACAUUUUAAUUUUUUAAUUUUUUUCUUUUAUUUUAUUGUUAUUAUACUUUAAGUUUUAGGGUACAUGUGUACAAUGUGCAGGUUAGUUACAUAUGUAUACAUGUGCCAUGCUAGUGUGCUGCACCCAUUAACUCGUCAUUUAGCAUUAGGUAUAUCUCCUAAUGCUAUCCCUCUCCCCUCCCCCCACCCCACAACAGUCCCCAGAGUGUGAUGUUCCCCUUCCUGUGUCCAUGUGUUCUCAUUGUUCAAUUCCCAUCUAUGAGUGAGAACAUGUGGUGUUUGGUUUUUUGUCCUUGCGAUAGUUUACUGAGAAUGAUGAUUUCCAAUUUCAUCCAUGUCCCUACAAAGGACAUGAACUCAUCCUUUUUUAUGGCUGCAUAGUAUUCCAUGGUGUAUAUGUGCCACAUUUUCUUAAUCCAGUCUAUCAUUGUUGGACAUUUGGGUUGGUUCCAAGUCUUUGCUAUUGUGAAUAGUGCUGCAAUAAACAUACGUGUGCAUGUGUCUUUAUAGCAGCAUGAUUUAUAGUCCUUUGAGUAUAUACCCAGUAAUGGGAUGGCUGGGUCAAAUGGUAUUUCUAGUUCUAGAUUCCUGAGGAAUCGCCACACUGACUUCCACAAUGGUUGAACUAGUUUACAGUCCCACCAACAGUGUAAAAGUGUUCCUAUUUCUCCACAUCCUCUCCAGCACCUGUUGUUUCCUGACUUUUUAAUGAUCGCCAUUCUAACUGGUGUGAGAUGGUAUCUCAUUGUGGUUUUGAUUUGCAUUUCUCUGAUGGUCAGUGAUGGUGAGCAUUUUUUCAUGUGUUUUUUGGCUGCAUAAAUGUCUUCUUUUGAGAAGUGUCUGUUCAUGUCCUUUGCCCACUUUUUGAUGGGGUUGUUUGUUUUUUUCUUGUAAAUUUGUUUGAGUUCAUUGUAGAUUCUGGAUAUUAGCCCUUUGUCAGAUGAGUAGGUUGCGAAAAUUUUCUGCCAUUUUGUAAGUUGCCUGUUCACUCUGAUGGUAGUUUCUUUUGCUGUGCAGAAGCUCUUGAGUUGAAUUAGAUCCCAUUUGUCAAUUUUGUCUUUUGUUGCCAUUGCUUUUGGUGUUUUAGACAUGAAGUCCUUGCCCAUGCCUAUGUCCUGAAUGGUAAUGCCUAGGUUUUCUUCUAGGGUUUUUAUGGUUUUAGGUCUGACAUGUAAGUCUUUAAUCCAUCUUGAAAUAAUUUUUGUAUAAGGUGUAAGGAAGGGAUCCAGUUUCAGCUUUCUACAUAUGGCUAGCCAGUUUUCCCAGCACCAUUUAUUCAAUAGGGAAUCCUUUCCCCAUUGCUUGUUUUUCUCAGGUUUGUCAAAGAUCAGAUAGCUGUAGACAUGCGGCGUUAUUUCUGAGGGCUCUUUUGUGUUCCAUUGAUCUAUAUCUCUGUUUUGGUACCAGUACCAUGCUGUUUUGGUUAUUGUAGCCUUGUAGUAUAGUUUGAAGUCAGGUAGCAUGAUGCCUCCAGCUUUGUUCUUUUGGCUUAGGAUUGACUUGGCGAUGCGGGCUCUUUUUUGGUUCCAUAUGAACUUUAAAGUAGUUUUUUCCAAUUCUGUGAAGAAAGUCAUUGGUAGCUUGAUGGGGAUGGCAUUGAAUCUAUAAAUUACCUUGGGCAGUAUGGCCAUUUUCACGAUAUUGAUUCUUCCUAUCCAUGAGCAUGGAAUGUUCUUCCAUUUGUUUGUAUCCUCUUUUAUUUCAUUGAGCAGUGGUUUGUAGUUCUCCUUGAAGAGGUCCUUCACGUCCCUUGUAAGUUGGAUUCCUAGGUAUUUUGUUCUCUUUGAAGCAAUUGUGAAUGGGAGUUCACUCAUGAUUUGGCUCUCUGUUUGUCUGUUAUUGGUGUAUAAGAAUGCUUGUGAUUUUUGUACAUUGAUUUUGUAUCCUGAGACUUUGCUGAAGUUGCUUAUCAGCUUAAGGAGAUUUUGGGCUGAGACAAUGGGGUUUUCUAGAUAUACAAUCAUGUCAUCUGCAAACAGGGACAAUUUGACUUCCUCUUUUCCUAAUUGAAUACUUUUUACUUCCUUCUCCUGCCUAAUUGCCCUGGCCAGAACUUCCAACACUAUGUUGAAUAGGAGUGGUGAGAGAGGGCAUCCCUGUCUUGUGCCAGUUUUCAAAGGGAAUGCUUCCAGUUUUUGCCCAUUCAGUAUGAUAUUGGCUGUGGGUUUGUCAUAGAUAGCUCUUAUUAUUUUGAGAUACGUCCCAUCAAUACCUGAUUUAUUGAGAGUUUUUAGCAUGAAGCGUUGUUGAAUUUUGUCAAAGGCCUUUUCUGCAUCUAUUGAGAUAAUCAUGUGGUUUUUGUCUUUGGUUCUGUUUAUAUGCUGGAUUACAUUGAUUGAUUUGCGUAUAUUGAACCAGCCUUGCAUCCCAGGGAUGAAGCCCACUUGAACAUGGUGGAUAAGCUUUUUGAUGUGCUGCUGGAUUUGGUUCGCCAGUAUUUUAUUGAGGAUUUUUAUUUUUAAUUUUUUGUUUUGUUUUUUGAGGCGAAGUCUCGCUCCGUUGCCAGGCUGGAGGGCAGUGGCACGAUCUCGACUCACUGCAACCUCCGCCUCCCAGGUUUAAGCAAUUCUCCUGUCUCAGCAGGAGUGGUUGGGAUUACAGGCACAUGCUGGCAUGCCUGUAUUUUUGUAUUUUUAGUAGAGACGGGGUUUCACCAUGUUGGCCAGGAUGGUCUCAAUCGCUUGACCUCAUGAUCCGCCCGCCUCGGCCUCCCAAAGUGCUGGGAUUACAGGCGUGAGCCACUGCACCCGGCCUACAUUUUAAUUUUUACAAAAAACUCUUAAACUUUUUUGUGAGCAGAAAUUCUCAAGUAUCGAAGCGUGGUGUUUUAGGCUCCAGAAGAAAUCCACUAUUACAGUGUCCUAGUAGCCCAGACAUAUGUGUUAAAUGACAUGUAUAUACUUUGUUAUUCUUUCUAAUAAAUAAUACUCUUUUACAA